AGCCGCUCUCCUCCCGCUCGCCGUUAGGGAGGCUCUGCACCUCAGCCGCCGCCUCUGUCGCCACUCUCUCCCCCUGUUCCGCGUCUGCGUCGCCACCACCGCCGGGGGUAUCCGGGGGGUCGCUUACCGGGCUGGCCCCGCGCCACAGCCGUAGCUUUAACCUCCCGUCAGCGGCCGCCCCAGGAAGAGGCUUCUCGGCCGCGGAGCCACUUGGGGCCUCAGUUCUCGCCCUCUUGCCGUCGCCGCGGGUCCUGGAGAAGCGGCCGCGGCCAGGGAACGGGGCAUCGCGGUUCCAACGAUUAACUGCUGAAGUACUGAUCGAGUUCUGCAUUUCUUCAAUGAGGAACUACAGGCUGAUCUUCUGCCAUAAUCUCAAACAGCCAUAAAUGACAAAAGAAUGCUUGCUCAGUGAGGGUAGCUGGUGCAGAAGCCAUUUUUUAAACUUAGGUAUUUAAGUACUGAAAGGCCGGGUGCGGUGGCUAACGCCUGUAAUCCCAGCACUUUGGGGGCCGAGACGGGCAGAUCACGAGGUCAGGAGAUGGAGACCAUCCUGGCUAACACGAAAAGACAGCUUUGAUUUCUGGCUGCAAAAAAGAUAUGAGGAAGAGCUCCUCCCCUUCCUUGAGUAACUGCAACUCCGUUCUUGCUAACAAAAUAUUUGGAAUUCCACUUGAUGAGCUGCAGCAGGGAGGACAUCCAGACAAUGAGGUUCCAUUCAUAGUCCGCCACGUUGUGGACUAUAUUGAGGAACAUGGAGGUCUGGAGCAACAAGGACUUUUUCAAGUCAAUGGAAAUGCUGAGACAGUGGAGUGGCUUCGGCAGAGAUACGACAGCGGAGAAGAGGUGGAUUUGGUUAAGGAAGCAGAUGUUCCCUCAGCUAUUAGCCUUCUUAGAUUUUUUCUUCAAGAACUUCCUGAACCUGUUAUCCCUGGCAGUUUACAUAUUCACUUGAUGCAGCUUUCUCAAGAUUAUAAUAAUGAAGAUGAAUUUGGAAGAAAGUUGAGGUUCCUCUUGCAACAGCUUCCACCUGUUAAUUAUAGUUUGUUAAAGUUUCUGUGUAGAUUUUUAGCCAAUGUAGCAUCACAUCAUGAAGAAAUUUGGUCCGCAAAUUCUUUGGCUGCUGUCUUUGGUCCAGAUGUCUUCCACAUUUACACAGAUGUGGAAGACAUGAAAGAGCAAGAAAUAGUGAGCAGGAUAAUGGCUGGACUUCUGGAAAACUACUAUGAGUUUUUUGAGAAUGAAGAGGAAGAUUUUUCAUCUAAUGAUUUGAGUUCAAUUACUGAACAGGUUAAUGAACUUUCUGAGGAAGAAGAGGAAGAUGAAAAGCUGGAACAUAUUGAAGAACUUCCAGAAGAGGGUGCAGAAAAAUCAAAUGACAUGCCAGAGGUGGUACAAUUAAGGAUGACUGAAAACAUCCUGGAAUCAAAUAGUGUUACGGCAACAAGCACCCAUAUAUCUCCCAUCAGCAUCCUACCAGCCUCUACAGAUAUUUUAGAAAGAACAAUUAGAGCAGCUGUGGAACAGCACCUUUUUGAUCUUCAGAGCAGCAUAGAUCAUGAUCUUAAGAAUUUACAACAGCAAAGUGUGGUGUGUAAUAAUGAAGCAGAAAGUAUUCAUUGUGAUGGGGAAGGAUCUAAUAACCAGAUUGAUAUUGCUGAUGAUAUUAUUAAUGCCAGUGAAAGUAACAGAGACUGUUCAAAACCUGUGGCUAGCACUAAUUUAGACAAUGAAGCUAUGCAGCAAGAUUGUGUAUUUGAGAAUGAAGAAAAUACCCAGUCUGUAGGUAUAUUGUUAGAGCCAUGCAGUGACCGUGGUGAUAGUGAAGAUGGCUGUCUUGAGAGGGAAGAAUAUUUGUUAUUUGACAGUGAUAAAUUGUCACACUUGAUUCUGGAUUCUAGUAGCAAGAUAUGUGAUUUGAAUGCCAACACUGAAUCAGAAGUACCAGGAGGUCAGAGUGUUGGUGUUCAAGGGGAAGCAGCGUGUGUCAGUAUUCCACAUUUAGAUCUGAAGAAUGUUUCUGAUGGUGAUAAAUGGGAAGCGUCAUGCCCUAUCACUUUUCCCCUCAUUGAUUUCAAAACAAUGCAUCUGCAGAGAGAUGGGGAGGAGCCAUUUCCUGCUUUUAAGUCUUGGCAGGAGGACUCUGAGUCUGGAGAAGCUCAGCUGUCUCCACAAGCUGGAAGAAUGAAUCAUCACCCCUUGGAAGAGGACUGUCCUCCAGUAUUAUCACACCGCAGUUUAGAUUUUGGUCAAAGCCAGCGUUUCCUACAUGAUCCAGAAAAGUUGGAUUCCUCAUCUAAAGCACUGUCUUUUACUAGAAUUCGAAGAUCAUCCUUUAGUUCAAAAGAUGAAAAGAGAGAGGACAGAACACCUUAUCAGCUGGUCAAGAAACUUCAGAAGAAAAUCAGACAAUUUGAGGAACAGUUUGAAAGGGAAAGAAAUAGCAAGCCCUCCUACAGUGAUAUUGCUGCCAAUCCAAAGGUAUUAAAAUGGAUGACAGAGCUUACAAAACUGCGGAAGCAAAUUAAAGAUGCAAAACACAAAAAUUCUGAUGGAGAAUUUGUACCUCAGACACGUCCACGUAGUAACACACUUCCAAAAAGCUUUGGCUCUUCUCUAGACCAUGAAGAUGAAGAGAAUGAAGAUGAACCCAAGGUCAUUCAGAAGGAGAAAAAACCAUCUAAAGAAGCAACCCUUGAACUUAUUCUUAAAAGACUGAAAGAAAAACGUAUUGAGAGGUGUCUUCCAGAAGAUAUCAAGAAAAUGACCAAAGAUCAUUUGGUAGAAGAGAAAGCUUCUCUUCAGAAAAGUCUUCUUUACUAUGAAAGUCAACAUGGAAGGCCGGUGACCAAGGAAGAAAGGCACAUUGUUAAACCUCUCUAUGAUAGAUACAGGCUUGUAAAACAAAUGCUGACAAGAGCUAGCAUCACUCCUGUCCUUGGAUCUCCAUCCACCAAGCGAAGGGGUCAGAUGUUACAGCCAAUCAUAGAAGGAGAAACUGCACAUUUUUUUGAAGAAAUCAAGGAGGAAGAAGAAGAUGGUGUUAAUCUGUCCUCUGAGUUAGGUGAUAUGUUGAAAACUGCAGUACAGGUACAGUCUUCAUUAGAAAACUCUGAAUCUGAUGUUGAAGAAAAUCAAGAAAAACUGGCUCUGGAUCUCCGAUUGUCAAGUUCUCGAGCAGCUUCUAUGCCUGAAUUAUUGGAACAACUUUGGAAAGCCAGAGCUGAAAAAAAGAAACUACGCAAAACGUUGCGGGAAUUUGAAGAAGCAUUUUAUCAACAAAAUGGAAGGAAUGCCCAGAAAGAGGAUCGUGUUCCAGUGCUUGAGGAGUACAGAGAGUACAAGAAAAUUAAAGCCAAGCUUAGGCUUCUUGAAGUUCUUAUAAGCAAACAAGAUUCUUCAAAAUCCAUAUAAGAUACGUUCCUUGAAAAUUCAUAUCAUAAAGUCAGUUGUAUUCCUUGAAGCUAUCAUCGUGUGUACUUGGCUGGUACUUAAAUUCGUUUUGUCAGGCACUCAGAGAAUCUCAUUUUGUACUUGGUUGUGGUGCCACUAAACAAAACAAAUGAUGGGAGAGUAAGUAGGCCCUCUCAAGGGAGCGUAAGUGAUGUUCCAUAUUAACCACAGACUGUCCUCUCCACCUUUAGCAAACAUAUGGUUUACUUCAUUGUUUUGUACUACAGAUACAUCCUUUUAGCAAAAGACUGGAAUUUUAUCCUUUCAACUUCAAGAACUUUGGAAAUGCAAGCUUUUUGUUAUUACCAACUUUUUGUUUCUCAUUACUGAAGAAAAUUGGAGGAAAAUCUUCAUACUGAAUUCUUCUGUUGCCUUUUUCUUACAGAAUGACUGAAAAUUUGAAAGAAAAGCCUAUAAAAGUGCACAUACGCAACUGUGUUCUCUGUUUUCCUAGAAAACCAAAAUCAAACUGAGAUUUCAAGUCGUACUAUGGAACACCUUUCUGUUUAAUUCCCAAAGUGACAUCUUCUCACAGGUAGUAUGUUAGUAAAAUUUUGCAAUUCGCUGGUCACACAGCUCCCGGAUGAAGAUAACAGUUGGUAGACCAAAAGGUGACCUCGCUUAGUAUAUUGAAAACACACACCACACAUCACACACAGAACUGAAUCAUACCACAUGCUGCCUAUGGGACUUCAGUUACUGUUUCCUGAGUUACUGUUUAUCCGCUGGCAAUGGUGUGAUUUGUCUGGAUCAGAUCCGCGCUAUUCCCCAACCCACCUCCAGAUAAUGUGAGAAAAUAGCCAUGUCAGUAUGUAGGAACUCUGAUGGUGCUCAGAUUUGUGUGUUCAAUCAAUGGGCUUAAAUCAGCAAAAUAUUAUGCCUAAAGUAAAUCUGUUCUUAACAAGGGCUCUACCACUGCAUUUUCACAUGUACCUUCAGGGGGUUAUCUUUUUUUUUUUCCCCUCCUAUUUUAAUCAGCAAAAUCCAUACCAAAACAACGACAACAACGCCCUCUUAAGGGACCACCCUUUGGUCAAUCAUAACAUGCUGUUUAAAGCAGCUGUUUACAGGAUGUGUAGUGGUAUGCCCCUUGUCAUAUACUCUUAGCAUAUCUUUUUUUCCUUUGGCUUUGCAUGGCUUUUCUUCAGGUACUGUCUCGGUAUCAUUCUGCUAAUCAUUGUUACAGAAUGGUGACUUCAUUUGUGCUAACAGUACAACAGCAGAUUUGGGUCAGGCUUAAUCUAAGUGUUAACUUUUUUUUCUGGUGCUUUUUUGGAUUGAUGACUGUCUCACUUUGACUAUACCCAUGUUUUGCAUGCAAUGACUCAUGCAUGGUUUUCUUAACUAGCUAAUAUUAACAAUUUAUUCCAUAUAAAAAUGGAAUUUUGCAACAUCCUUUAAUAAGGUGAGGGAAGCAUGAACCUCAGACUUCUGGCACUAUUACAUAGUAAGCACAUGAAGUAGUUUGAUAAUAAAUAGCAGUUCUAGUACUUCACAUUUCACCCGUGUGUGCAAUGCCUUUUUCUGGGGGGUGGGGGGUGAGGGAAAACCUGGUAGUGAAUGUGUAGUUGGGGAAUAAAGAAAAGCACUAAAUCCUGCCCUUUUUGUGUGGUUUCCUUUUGAUACAACUAGGUUAUUCAUAAUGUAUACCUAGAAAAGUGAAAUUGAAAAUACCAAAAGAUGUAUCAUUUUUAUUUGAAUCCAUCAUGCAGUGUACAUUUCAGAUAAUUUCCUUCAGUCUCCAGAUAGGAGUGUAUCCAAACAUCUAAUUUUAUGUGCACUGUGUAUCUUAUAUGAAUGUUUUAUUUUAUAUACCACAUGCAAAAAUGUCCAUAUGCACUAUUUAAAUGUUUUAAAUAAUAUAUUCCUUCUUUAUAAUGCUAAAUCUAUAUGAGUACCAUAUUUUUAUAAGUCAGUGGUCUGACUGGUUUCAUUUUAGAAUUAACAGCUGCUUCAAUAUGUUAUUCAAUGUUAAUGUUUGGCUGUGAGUAGAAUAUGUAAAAGUGGCAUGGCAGCACUUAUGCUCUGUGACAGUAUUGUGUGUCAUAGUUGAGCAGUAGCUGGUAGAAUUAGGCAGUUGGUGAUAGUUUUACUUUGGUACAAAUAAAAACUGUAUAUCUAUAUACAAAUAAUAUAUAGAUAUAUAUGUCCACCAGUAUAAUGGCAUUGCUGUGUCUGGCACUUCAUUGUACAGACUUUUAUAAUAAAAGAACUUGAAAGUUCUAA